AGAGACAGAAGGUGGAUAGACAAAUCUCCACCUUCAGACUGGUAGGCUCCUCCAGAAGCCAUCAGACAGGAAGAUGUGAAAAUCCCCAGCACUCAUCCCAGAAUCACUAAGUGGCACCUGUCCUGGGCCAAAGUCCCAGGACAGACCUCAUUGUUCCUCUGUGGGAAUACCUCCCCAGGAGGGCAUCCUGGAUUUCCCCCUUGCAACCCAGGUCAGAAGUUUCAUCGUCAAGGUUGUUUCAUCUUUUUUUUCCUGUCUAACAGCUCUGACUACCACCCAACCUUGAGGCACAGUGAAGACAUCGGUGGCCACUCCAAUAACAGCAGGUCACAGCUGCUCUUCUGGAGGUGUCCUACAGGUGAAAAGCCCAGCGACCCAGUCAGGAUUUAAGUUUACCUCAAAAAUGGAAGAUUUUAACAUGGAGAGUGACAGCUUUGAAGAUUUCUGGAAAGGUGAAGAUCUUAGUAAUUACAGUUACAGCUCUACCCUGCCCCCUUUUCUACUAGAUGCCGCCCCAUGUGAACCAGAAUCCCUGGAAAUCAACAAGUAUUUUGUGGUCAUUAUCUAUGCCCUGGUAUUCCUGCUGAGCCUGCUGGGAAACUCCCUCGUGAUGCUGGUCAUCUUAUACAGCAGGGUCGGCCGCUCCGUCACUGAUGUCUACCUGCUGAACCUAGCCUUGGCCGACCUACUCUUUGCCCUGACCUUGCCCAUCUGGGCCGCCUCCAAGGUGAAUGGCUGGAUUUUUGGCACAUUCCUGUGCAAGGUGGUCUCACUCCUGAAGGAAGUCAACUUCUAUAGUGGCAUCCUGCUACUGGCCUGCAUCAGUGUGGACCGUUACCUGGCCAUUGUCCAUGCCACACGCACACUGACCCAGAAGCGCUACUUGGUCAAAUUCAUAUGUCUCAGCAUCUGGGGUCUGUCCUUGCUCCUGGCCCUGCCUGUCUUACUUUUCCGAAGGACCGUCUACUCAUCCAAUGUUAGCCCAGCCUGCUAUGAGGACAUGGGCAACAAUACAGCAAACUGGCGGAUGCUGUUACGGAUCCUGCCCCAGUCCUUUGGCUUCAUCGUGCCACUGCUGAUCAUGCUGUUCUGCUACGGAUUCACCCUGCGUACGCUGUUUAAGGCCCACAUGGGGCAGAAGCACCGGGCCAUGCGGGUCAUCUUUGCUGUCGUCCUCAUCUUCCUGCUCUGCUGGCUGCCCUACAACCUGGUCCUGCUGGCAGACACCCUCAUGAGGACCCAGGUGAUCCAGGAGACCUGUGAGCGCCGCAAUCACAUCGACCGGGCUCUGGAUGCCACCGAGAUUCUGGGCAUCCUUCACAGCUGCCUCAACCCCCUCAUCUACGCCUUCAUUGGCCAGAAGUUUCGCCAUGGACUCCUCAAGAUUCUAGCUAUACAUGGCUUGAUCAGCAAGGACUCCCUGCCCAAAGACAGCAGGCCUUCCUUUGUUGGCUCUUCUUCAGGGCACACUUCCACUACUCUCUAAGACCUCCUGCCUAAGUGCAGCCCCGUGGGGUUCCUCCCUUCUCUUCACAGUCACAUUCCAAGCCUCAUGUCCACUGGUUCUUCUUGGUCUCAGUGUCAAUGCAGCCCCCAUUGUGGUCACAGGAAGUAGAGGAGGCCACGUUCUUACUAGUUUCCCUUGCAUGGUUUAGAAAGCUUGCCCUGGUGCCUCACCCCUUGCCAUAAUUACUAUGUCAUUUGCUGGAGCUCUGCCCAUCCUGCCCCUGAGCCCAUGGCACUCUAUGUUCUAAGAAGUGAAAAUCUACACUCCAGUGAGACAGCUCUGCAUACUCAUUAGGAUGGCUAGUAUCAAAAGAAAGAAAAUCAGGCUGGCCAACGGGGUGAAACCCUGUCUCUACUAAAAAUACAAAAAAAAAAAAAAAUUAGCCGGGCGUGGUGGUGAGUGCCUGUAAUCACAGCUACUUGGGAGGCUGAGAUGGGAGAAUCACUUGAACCCGGGAGGCAGAGGUUGCAGUGAGCCGAGAUUGUGCCCCUGCACUCCAGCCUGAGCGACAGUGAGACUCUGUCUCAGUCCAUGAAGAUGUAGAGGAGAAACUGGAACUCUCGAGCGUUGCUGGGGGGGAUUGUAAAAUGGUGUGACCACUGCAGAAGACAGUAUGGCAGCUUUCCUCAAAACUUCAGACAUAGAAUUAACACAUGAUCCUGCAAUUCCACUUAUAGGAAUUGACCCACAAGAAAUGAAAGCAGGGACUUGAACCCAUAUUUGUACACCAAUAUUCAUAGCAGCUUAUUCACAAGACCCAAAAGGCAGAAGCAACCCAAAUGUUCAUCAAUGAAUGAAUGAAUGGCUAAGCAAAAUGUGAUAUGUACCUAACGAAGUAUCCUUCAGCCUGAAAGAGGAAUGAAGUACUCAUACAUGUUACAACACGGACGAACCUUGAAAACUUUAUGCUAAGUGAAAUAAGCCAGACAUCAACAGAUAAAUAGUUUAUGAUUCCACCUACAUGAGGUACUGAGAGUGAACAAAUUUACAGAGACAGAAAGCAGAACAGUGAUUACCAGGGACUGAGGGGAGGGGAGCAUGGGAAGUGACGGUUUAAUGGGCACAGGGUUUAUGUUUAGGAUGUUGAAAAAGUUCUGCAGAUAAACAGUAGUGAUAGUUGUACCGCAAUGUGACUUAAUGCCACUAAAUUGACACUUAAAAAUGGUUUAAAUGGUCAAUUUUGUUAUGUAUAUUUUAUAUCAAUUUAAAAAAAAACCUGAGCCCCAAAAGGUAUUUUAAUCACCAAGGCUGAUUAAACCAAGGCUAGAACCACCUGCCUAUAUUUUUUGUUAAAUGAUUUCAUUCAAUAUCUUUUUUUUAAUAAACCAUUUUUACUUGGGUGUUUA